ACUGAGGGGCACCAGAGGAGCAGACUACAAGAAUGGCACACGCUAUGGAAAACUCCUGGACAAUCAGUAAAGAGUACCAUAUUGAUGAAGAAGUGGGCUUUGCUCUGCCAAAUCCACAGGAAAAUCUACCUGAUUUUUAUAAUGACUGGAUGUUCAUUGCUAAACAUCUGCCUGAUCUCAUAGAGUCUGGCCAGCUUCGAGAAAGAGUUGAGAAGUUAAACAUGCUCAGCAUUGAUCAUCUCACAGACCACAAGUCACAGCGCCUUGCACGUCUAGUUCUGGGAUGCAUCACCAUGGCAUAUGUGUGGGGCAAAGGUCAUGGAGAUGUCCGUAAGGUCUUGCCAAGAAAUAUUGCUGUUCCUUACUGCCAACUCUCCAAGAAACUGGAACUGCCUCCUAUUUUGGUUUAUGCAGACUGUGUCUUGGCAAACUGGAAGAAAAAGGAUCCUAAUAAGCCCCUGACUUAUGAGAACAUGGACGUUUUGUUCUCAUUUCGUGAUGGAGACUGCAGUAAAGGAUUCUUCCUGGUCUCUCUAUUGGUGGAAAUAGCAGCUGCUUCUGCAAUCAAAGUAAUUCCUACUGUAUUCAAGGCAAUGCAAAUGCAAGAACGGGACACUUUGCUAAAGGCGCUGUUGGAAAUAGCUUCUUGCUUGGAGAAAGCCCUUCAAGUGUUUCACCAAAUCCACGAUCAUGUGAACCCAAAAGCAUUUUUCAGUGUUCUUCGCAUAUAUUUGUCUGGCUGGAAAGGCAACCCCCAGCUAUCAGACGGUCUGGUGUAUGAAGGGUUCUGGGAAGACCCAAAGGAGUUUGCAGGGGGCAGUGCAGGCCAAAGCAGCGUCUUUCAGUGCUUUGACGUCCUGCUGGGCAUCCAGCAGACUGCUGGUGGAGGACAUGCUGCUCAGUUCCUCCAGGACAUGAGAAGAUAUAUGCCACCAGCUCACAGGAACUUCCUGUGCUCAUUAGAGUCAAAUCCCUCAGUCCGUGAGUUUGUCCUUUCAAAAGGUGAUGCUGGCCUGCGGGAAGCUUAUGACGCCUGUGUGAAAGCUCUGGUCUCCCUGAGGAGCUACCAUCUGCAAAUCGUGACUAAGUACAUCCUGAUUCCUGCAAGCCAGCAGCCAAAGGAGAAUAAGACCUCUGAAGACCCUUCAAAACUGGAAGCCAAAGGAACUGGAGGCACUGAUUUAAUGAAUUUCCUGAAGACUGUAAGAAGUACAACUGAGAAAUCCCUUUUGAAGGAAGGUUAAUGUAACCCAACAAGAGCACAUUUUAUCAUAGCAGAGACAUCUGUAUGCAUUCCUGUCAUUACCCAUUGUAACAGAGCCACAAACUAAUACUAUGCAAUGUUUUACCAAUAAUGCAAUACAAAAGACCUCAAAAUACCUGUGCAUUUCUUGUAGGAAAACAACAAAAGGUAAUUAUGUGUAAUUAUACUAGAAGUUUUGUAAUCUGUAUCUUAUCAUUGGAAUAAAAUGACAUUCAAUAAAUAAAAAUGCAUAAGAUAUAUUCUGUCGGCUGGGCGCGGUGGCUCACGCCUGUAAUCCCAGCACUUUGGGAGGCCGAGGCGGGCGGAUCACAAGGUCAGGAGAUCGAGACCAUCUUGGCUAACACGGUGAAACCCCGUCUCUACUAAAAAUACAAAAAAUUAGCCGGGCGCGGUGGCGGGCACCUGUAGUCCCAGCUACUCGGGAGGCUGAGGCAGGAGAAUGGCGUGAACCUGGGAGGCGGAGCUUGCAGUGAGCCAAGAUUGUGCCACUGCAAUCCGGCCUGGGCUAAAGAGCGGGACUCCGUCUCAAAAAAAAAAAAAAAAAGAUAUAUUCUGUCAUAAUAAAUAAAAAUGCAUAAGAUAUAA